GCAGUGGGUAUGUAUCUUGGGGUCCGGAGAAGAGUUUAGUCCUGGGUGUCAAACCAAGAGUCCAGUCCCAAUGCUGCUUCCAGCAUGCUGGGCCCUCCCAGAGAGGCAAUGGGGGUGGAGGUGGGGGAUCAGUUUUCUUAUCUCUAAAAAGAGGGAGCAAGGUUCAAUGACAUUAUCUCAACGGGGUGUUUCUCAAAGGGCUCUGGGCUCACUCGGACUUAAAACUCUGUAUUCAAGUCCCAAUCCUGCUUAUUAGCCGCCACCCUGAGCAAGGAACUUCACUUCCUUGGGCCUCAGUUUUCUUGUCUGUAGGAUGGGGCAGCAUUACAUAGCUCACCUGCUAGUUUCCCUCAGGAUGUGGUAGAGGUCAAGUUAUAGACUUUAUGUGAAGGUACAUGAGGGAACCCCCUGAUAAAUGAGAGGUGUUAUUAUGACCUAUGGUUAAAUUAAGGUUCUAUGAGUUUUAAGGUUUUUGGAAGUUAGUCCAAGAAUGGGGAAAUCUUAUUAAAAUAACUCAUGGUCUACUGCUCUCUUGGAUGGGAAUGUAGAGGCUGGGAGGUGGAUUAUAACCCACAGUCCUGACCGACUCCUCACACAGUGUUGCAUUGCCCGUGGUCUUGGAUAGAGGACAGAAUGGGGUGGGGAGGGCAUGGGUGUCUAUACCUAGGCACACGUGAUUGUGUGACUCCAUGUGCAUAGGUCAUGGUAGGUGUGUAUGUGACUGUGAUUACCUCCAUCAGUGUGAAAUAGCAGGUUUCUCCCCUAAGUCCAUGUGUAAGUGCGUGCAUGUGUAUCUAUGCUUACAUGAGGCCAUUUGGUGUAGAAUAGAGAAUGUAGGAUUUGAAUCGGGAGAAGUGGGAGAGUCUCAGCUCUCUGCUUCCCGGCUAUGUGACCUUGGGCGUGUCUCUUAAUGGUCCGGAGCCUCAGUGCCCCACUGUUAGCCCAUCUGAUUCACUGCUCCUGGCAAAGAUGAAAUGAGAUCAUGUCAAUGAAACGGCUCUCUGGACGCCGUGUGGCUGCAUGAAGCCCGAUGGAGAAUCCAAGGUGCCCAAGGAGGCCCCUGGCGGAGAAGAAAGCCAGGUCUCUGGACAGGCCGCAGGCCCCCGGGAAAGGCUCGGAGUCGUGGGACUGCCAUUGGCUCUCCCUGCCCACUGCCCCCUCCAGGAAGGCGCUUCACUGGACGACCAGUGAUUGGGCCAGACAUUCAGACAGCCCAGCUCCAUCUGCAGAGGCUCACUGCACCACCGCUGCAGCCCCCACUCCCGAGGAGACCGGAGAUUUUCUCCCCAGCGAGCAGAGGCCUUCGCAAGACACCAAGAAGGGGUGGCUGAAGACCAUGCUGAACUUCUUCGUGAGGACGGGCCCUGAGGAGCCCAGAGAAAAGGCCAGCAGGAGGCCAAGGGGGAAGGAGGGUAUCUCCCAGCAUCCGGAGCCCCUGGAAGCAGCAGGGGAGCCAGCCCUCAGGAAGAAAGCCCACCACGACAAGAAGCCCAGCCGCAAGAAGCAAGGUCACAAGAAACACGCGGCCGAGGUGACUAAGGCAGCUCAAGACCAGGAGGCCAGAGGCCGAGAGGAAGGGUUGUCCAAGGCAGCUGCUGCCUUGCGCUCCGGGGAGGCUGACCUGGGCCCAGCUCGCAGGGGUGGGGAAGAUUCUGAUCACCAGUCCUUCCUCAUCAAAGUGGAUGGUACUGGAGCUUUGGAUGUUUCUCCCCAUGCCACAGGUCAUCAGCAAGAAGAGGAGCUCAAAAAGCCUGACCAGGAUGCUAUCAUUCAGAUGAUAGUGGAAUUGCUCAAAAGAGUGGGAGACCAGUGGGAAGAAGAGCAAUCUCUGGCCUCACAGCUGGGGGUGGCCCUGCCAAACCCAGCACCAGCUGUUAGGAAGAAAUCCCAAGAGAAAAAGACAAGCCUCAAGAGAACCUCAAAGACAAACCCCAAGAAACACGGCUCCGAGGAGGCCAAGAGGGGGGCUGCAGAUGUUUCCAGUCCAGAGGCCUGGCCACCCAAGAAGUCCAGCUUUCUGCCCCUGUGUGUCAGCGGCCAUCGGCCUUCCAUCUCCAGCAGCUAUGGCUUGGAAGAACCUAAAGUCCAGGAGGCCCCAUCUACAGAGGCUGGGGCUCCAGGUCCCUCCGUGCUUCCCACCCCAUCAGAGAGCCAGGAACCUGGAGAGGAGCUUCCGCUGGACAGAGCCUCGGAAUACAAAGAAUUCAUUCAGAAGAUCAUUUCCAUGCUCCAAGAUGCAGAAGAACAGCAAGGAGAGGAGCAACCUCAAGUCCAGCAGGAAGAGGUGGGUGUAGAAAACCCGGCCCCACACUGCAGAAGGAAAUCUCAAGAAAAAAGGUCGAGCUUCAGGAGAGCGUUUUACCAUAAGAAACACACCUCCAAGGAACCCAGAAGAGCGGGGGCAGCAGGGGCUGCCAGCCCAGAGGCCCGACGACCCAAGAGGCCCAGCUUUCUGCCCCUGUGUGUUGGUGGCCAUCGGCCCUCCACCUCCAGCAGCCUUGAUCCAGAAGAUCUCGAGUGCCGGGAGCCCCUGCCCGCAGAAGGGGAGCCAGUUGUGAUCUCAGAAGCACCCUCCCAGGCUAGAGGCCACACGCCAGAAGGGGCACCUCAGCUGAGUGGAGCAUGUGAAUCUAAGGAGAUCAUCAUCCAGAAGCUUGUGGCACUUCUCCAAGAAGUGGAUGGCCAACUGGGGCAGCAGAUCAGGCGCCACCCCAGCUUUAAGAGGUUUUUUUACGAGUUCUCGGACUCCUCCCUCAGCAAGCUGGUAGCCACCCUGCGCAGCCAGGUGGCUCACUCCUCUAAGCUGGACAGGAACCGCGCCAGGAGACUCUACCAGUUUGACGUUAGCUUAGCUAACAAAUUUGCUGGCAGCAACAGCCAUGCCAUGUGCAUCCUCAUGGGCCUAAGAGACCACUACAAUUGCACCCAGUUCCCAUACAGGGAGGACCAGCCGAACAUCACAAGUCCUAAGGUUGAAAGUCCAGAUUGAAAGCUGUGUCUUGCACUCAAAUUCCCUUGAACUAGCCAAAUGGUUCGCAGCUUUAGCCAGGAGACCCUGAAGAUGCUCUGUGAUGUCCCAAUCCCUGCUUCACAAACGUGAUGGAAGACAAGAGCAGACAAUCAUUCUGUGUCCAUACCCUAGUAUCUGAGAAGCACAGAGCAUUCUUCCACAAGGCAAGACACAGAGGCCAUGUCUGGGGAAAUCAGCACUGGACUGGGAAUGAGGAAGACUGGGGCUCUACCUGCUGAACCUACCCCAGACUUGCUGCAUGACCCUCUACACAUUCCCCCUCCUCUCCAGACUUUGGAGUCUAGGAUCCCACCCAGAAGGCCUACUGAUAUUUUCUCAGAUGUUCAUGUUAACUGAGUCUAGUUUUUAAACUAAAUUUUUAUUUAAUCUCUAAACAGAACAUCCACAUGCAUCCAAACAGAUAUGCAUCGAAGUGUAUCCCAUCAUUUCUUCAGUUGACCAGUAGUUCUUCAUGCUCAUAUGGAUUUGUAGAUGCCUCCCAGGAACUCUGCAGGCCCAAGAUGGAAAAACCUAGAGACUGGGGACACUUGGUCUCUCAGAAUCCUUCUAACCCUGUGUCCUGUCAUUCUAUGACUAGAGAAAUGGAGCUGAUACCUUGCACCUCUCCCAUCUCAUGGGAUUGGCUAGGAGUCAGUGAGAAAAUGGAUGUGAAGAGUUCUGAAAAUUACCUAGUGCCAUGUCCAUGUAGGCACUAUAGCUUCUUUUGGGUAGUUUUCAGGAAGUGGAGGAGGGCUUCAAUGGGCUGGACUGCCAUGGAUUGUUGCACAGGGGUGCACUGCUCAAGAGCACCAUACUCCAGGAGGUACUAUUCAUGUCCUAGACAUUGUGGAUUUGUAGAUUUAUCAUGACAGUUUUGCAGCUGGUAGCAGUAACAUGUCUUGAGAAAAGGGCUAUUUUUUGUAUUUGCACAAAGGUGAAGUGUGGGGGUGCCAGAGGCUCUGCCUUCUGUAUAGCUCAACAGUUUCAAUAGCUUGACUCAGGUGUGAAAUUUGCCACAUGUUCAUAUCUAUGUGCAGGAAGGACAAGACUGUAGACAGACAGUCGGCUCCCUUGGACACUGCCCAGAACAUGUGGUCAUGGGGGAAAGGGUGUUAAACCUGGAUGGCAAGUGAGAUCUUGUGACCCUUGGGGACAUGGUAUUGCCGUGUUGAACCUGCUGUCGCACCAUGGGGUAGGACUGGGGAGGAGGAGCAGUCUAGAGCGGAGAGGCCCUGGGUGCUUAUAUGGGACUGGCCUCCAACCUGAGGCACUGGCUUCAUAAGCUCAACUCAGCCUAUCCGGAAAGCCAUUUAGUUUUUAUUGCUGCUUCUGAGAAGUGGGGGAGAGGUGAGCUAUUUGUGGAUUUGUUUUAGGCAGUGUUCACAAUCAUAGCACCUAAAUAUGAAGGAUCAGAAUAAGUUAUGAAAUGAAGGUCAGGAACCUUUUGUACAUAGUUUCUUAUUUGGAAUGAUGUUCUUUAAGCCCUAUGAGUAUUUGGUAUGUGCUCCUGAUGCUGGCAUCUGAGUCUCAUUUUUGUACCGUGUUAUUUGAGCAAAUAAAUACAUUAACUUGCA